AUUCGGGAGCCAGUUGUUGGCUUGGGUGGGCGGACAGCGCCCGGUCGGCGGCUGCUCUGCCCGGAGGCCCGCCUGUGCCUAGGUGUUUGAGGGGUUCGUUGGUGAGUGGGAGGCUCCUCCAGGCUUGAAGCUGAGCAGCGCUCGCCGAGGCCGGCGCCUUCGAGCCGGUAGCUGCGGGCUUCGGUUCCCGCUGCACUCCGGCUUCAUCCAUUUCUGAUCGCCCAGGACCACACCGCAGCGUAACUGCAGGCCUCUCAGCGAAAAAGGGGGAAAGCAAAGACCCGGGUGUGCAUCCUCUUCCUCGGCUUCCGCCCCUUUCCGGCGGAGUGGAGAUCCUAUUCAGAGGGGCCGGUCUCUCUAAAUAUGCCCCAGGAUGACCGAGCGGCCGCCGAGCGAGGCGGCUCGCAGUGACCCCCAGCUAGAGGGACGGGACGCGGCCGAGGCCAGCAUGGCCCCCCCGCACCUGGUCCUGCUGAACGGCGUCGCCAAGGAGACGAGCCGCGCGGCCGCAGCGGAGCCCCCAGUCAUCGAACUGGGCGCGCGCGGAGGCCCGGGGGGCGGCCCUGCCGGUGGGGGCGGCGCCGCGAGAGACUUAAAGGGCCGCGACGCGGCGACGGCCGAAGCGCGCCAUCGGGUGCCCACCACCGAGCUGUGCAGACCUCCCGGGCCCGCCCCGGCCCCCGCGCCCGCCUCGGUUACAGCGGAGCUGCCCGGCGACGGCCGCAUGGUGCAGCUGAGUCCUCCCGCGCUGGCUGCCCCCGCCGCCCCCGGCCGCGCGCUGCUCUACAGCCUCAGCCAGCCGCUGGCCUCUCUCGGCAGGUCAGGGGCCAGGGGCCAGGGGCCAGGGGCUGGGCGGGUGGGCAGGGCGACCACCCCCACCGGGGUUUCCUUCUACACAUCGGCGGCGGCCUGCCCUGGGGGCCGAGCGGGUGGAGCGCAGGGAGAGGAGGUCGUUUUAAACCCAGUGGCUCUAGAGCCUCAAGCUGGAGCCCCCGACGGGUUCUUUGGGGAGCCGGAUGCCUUCCCUAUGUUCACCACCAACAAUCGAGUGAAGAGGAGACCUUCCCCCUAUGAGAUGGAGAUUACUGAUGGUCCCCACACCAAAGUUGUGCGGCGUAUCUUCACCAACAGCCGGGAGCGAUGGCGGCAGCAGAAUGUGAACGGGGCCUUUGCCGAGCUCCGCAAGCUGAUCCCCACACAUCCCCCGGACAAGAAGCUCAGCAAGAAUGAGAUCCUCCGCCUGGCCAUGAAGUAUAUCAACUUCUUGGCCAAGCUGCUCAAUGACCAGGAGGAGGAGGGCACCCAGCGGGCCAAGACUGGCAAGGACCCUGUGGUGGGGGCUGGUGGGGGUGGAGGUGGGGGAGGGGGCGGCGCGCCCCCAGAUGACCUCCUGCAAGACGUGCUUUCCCCCAACUCCAGCUGCGGCAGCUCCCUGGAUGGGGCAGCCAGCCCGGACAGCUACACGGAGGAGCCCGCGCCCAAGCACACGGCCCGCAGCCUCCAUCCUGCCAUGCUGCCUGCCGCCGAUGGAGCCGGCCCUCGGUGAUGGGUCUGGGCCACCAGGAUCAGCCAGGAGGGCGUUCUUAGGCUGCUGGGAUGGUGGGCUUCAGGGCAGGUGGGGUGAGAAUUGGGCGGCUCUGAAGCAAGGCGGUGGACUUGAACUUUCCUGGAUGUCUGAACUUUGGGAAGCCUUUACUGACCCUGGGGCUGGCUUUUCUGUUUCCUGUACCAGUAGGAGAUCAGAAAAAUGGAGCAAAGUGGUAGGUACUUUUUGUGAAGACGGCACGGUCUUCCCUCUUCCCUCAGUCCCAAAUCCUUCCCAAGUAAGAGGCUGGAGUUGUCACUGCUUUUGGCCUGGAGUUUGGGAUCCCUGUCUUUCCUAAGACCUGGGGUUGUCAGCUCUCAUCUGAGGCAUCCAGCAGUCUCUGCCUUGCCUUUAGCCCCUCCCAAGCUGGCUGGGGUGGCCUGUGUGGCCACUUCUGUCCAUAUUUAUAGGUACCCAAUAGCUGCCCAUUUCGUGAGCCCCAUCUUCACCCAGGCCUAUGUUGAUCCAUCCAGCUUGCCAGAUGCUGCAGAGUCACAAGCCUCGAGGUGCCUUCUUCAGGGCCUGGUUGAAGAAGAUGAUCAGUGGACAGUCUGCUCUAGAUGAGCUGGGCCGGAGGGUCAGGAAACCCAGUCGCCCUUACUUCUUGCCCUGGGGAUCAAAGUUCUGCUUUCUCCCCAAUGAGACUUGCCUUCCUAAGCCUGUGGCUGUGGAGACAAUGUCUGCAGCCCUGAGAAAGCCCUGUCGGGCUUUGUGUGAAGGCAGAGAAAGGGACAAUGAUAGUAGAGUGAUAUGGAGCAAGAGAUAUUUUGGGCAUGUGGGCUUCAACUCCUCGACAUCACUGUUCAUGCUGGCGAGUGAAUGCCAGUGUGCUGAUGGGCGUACGCUGGUGCUGAGUAGAUGCGCAGCCCCAUCUGUGCAUUCUCCUGGAUGCUUAGAGGGAUUUCUUUGCUGUAAGAUGUCUGUUUGCUGAUGGUCUGGUCUAUGUUCCGAAUUGAGCACAAAACCUGUCCUAUGAAUGCUUUGCAUUUGGAAUUUUUGCUUGACUUCAGUUAUUGGUGGAAUCUUUAGCGCUCAAUAGGACCAGGAUCCAGCCUCACUUCUAGGGUAUGGGAAAUCCAAUCAGAGACCAGGCCCUGGCUAAGACCCAAACAUAUGCACAUUCACUUAGCAGAACCUUAAACACCCCUCAGUUGUGCAGCUUUUGGUCAUCAAGGGUGCGUCUGGGAGGUUGGUUUAAUGCAAUAGAAGUGCUCCCCUCUGAAAGUUGUACAUGAAAUUUUUGUAAAUCACAUCCUUAUCCUUCAUCUUUUAAAGAAAUAACCACUGCAAGUCCUUUUGUAAAGUGAAGAAUCCUUUUGUAGAAUGAACCACUGCCCCUUCAUUGAUUUCCUGUGUCAAUCCAGAUGGUGGGAUGUGGUUUUCUUAAGGUGAGGCCUGUCUGUGACCUGCAUCUAAGCCCAUGGGACAAAUUGCACAGAAGUCCUGUAUGUCUGUCAUUGUACCCUUAAGUCACCCUAGCCCUCUCCCUCUAGGCUCUGCCUUCGAGGUCAGAGGAGAGAUAGCCUGUGGCCCUGUCCUGCCAUGCAAGAACUCAUCACUGUGGCUGUCUGGAAAGCCCCCCCUUAUAGUUUGGGCUUCAGCCUAGUGGCUUGUCCUCACCAUGAUGGGGCCCUAAUUCAGCCAUGUACAGACAGAGAAUAUGUCUGCUCCUUUCCCCUUCCUUUUAAGUAAGGUCCAAUUCUCGAGCUUGGGGCAACAUUGUUCACCUUUGUAGCACUCAGGCUCUCCAUUCAAUUUCAGGCUCCCCAGAUCAUGUUUUGGUGAAAAUUAGGGUUGGUUCCUUUCCAACGUUUGGAAGAUCCUGUGAGGAGCCCCAUCUGUCUAAAGAUAGAGUCAUUGCUGUAGGAUCUAAGGCUGUUUGCUUCACCGUGGAUUCGCUUGAGUUAGGAAUGAGAAGUAGCCACAGUAUGGAUGGGUGGAUGGGUUUUAUGAGAUGGAUCACAUAUUUUAUUAAGAACUCAAACUUCUGGCUCCCUCUUCUUUCAGACUUGCCAUGUGACUCUGGCUUGGCCUAUCUCCUAGGGCUAUGGUGUGGACUGAAUGGGAUCAUGAAAGUAGACAGUUUUGAGAACGUAAAGAACUUUUUCUUUUCCCUCAAUCUCAAUCCUGCAGUGGGGUUUCGCAGCCUGAGUCCACGACCUAGGCAGUAGGCCGGUGUGCCUGACUGCCCAGCAUUUGGGUAAUUUAGAUUGUAAACCGCUUUGGCCUGAGUUAUUGAGAUUGUCCUCAUUUCUCCAGAUUAUCUAUUUGUGUGUGUGUGUGUGUGUGUGUGAGAGACGGUGUCUUGUUCUGUCACUCAGGCUGGAGUACAGUGGUGCCAUCAUUGCUGUCUGCAGCCUUGAACUCUGGGCUCAAGCAAUCCUCUCACCUCAGCCUCCCGAGUAGGGAGGACCACAGGUGUGAGCCACCACACCUGGCUAAUUUUUACUUUUUUUUUUUUUUGGUAGAGAUGGAGUCUUGCUAUAUUGCCCAGGCUGGUCUUGAAGUCCUGGCUUCAGGCAAUUCUCCUGCCUUUGCCUCCAGAAGCACUGGGAUCACAGGUGUCAGCCAUUGCACCCAGCCCAGAUUGUCUUAAUUUCUAUCUUGUUCCAAGGCCAGGGACAGUAAUAAGAAUGGAAAAGAGAUAUGGGAACACUGGCAGACUGUGUAAAAUGUAAUGCAACUACCCAAAACAAGCCUGGUAGGAAAGGGCAAGUCUUUAGGUCUUUGUAAGAACUAAAGAAGAUCUGUAAUUUUUAUUUUCACCCUCUGUACCCCAUGACCUUAUCCUUCCUCUCCUUCCUUGUUACCCAUGAAAAACUGGCAACAUUCCAAGAAUAGCAUCUGUACAAAGGGGAAAGAACAUAAAGGUAAAACAAAACAAAACAACAUUUUGAGAACAAAGAUGACCAUAACCACUGAAGGGAAUCACAUCUUUUAAGACAAAUUCAUAUUCUUUUAUUUGUUAUGGCAGAUGACAAGAUGGUACAACCUUUAUUCUUUUCCAAAAUAAAACAAAGGGCACAGCAUCUGUAGUCAGCCGACAACUAUUUCGGCCUUUUGGGGGUGGGUCUGGCCGUACUUGUGAUUUCGAUGGUACGUGACCCUCUGCUGAAGACUUGCCCCCUGCCCGUGUACAUAGUGCAUUGUUUCUGUGGGCGGGCCCAGCACUUUCCGUCAACGUUGUACUGUAUGUGAUGAAUUGCGUUGGUCUCUGCAUUUUUCUGCAGAAGAGGAGUAACCGCUCCAGGUACCUUGACCUUUGUACAGCCCAGAGGCCAACACUGUGGGUGUGUGACUCUUUAGCAAAAAAAACCCAUGUGGUGAUGAUGUGUAUAUAUAUGUGAGGAUGUAUCGGGAAGAUUUCUAAAUAAAAGUUUUACAAAGGGGC